AGGCCUCUGCUGGCAUGAGCCCUAAGUGCCGGGCACUGACCACAGCCGGCGGCCGGAGGGUCAGGAGGGCCUUGGAGGAGAGAUGCCCGGCAAACAGUCUGAGGAAGGGCCGGCGGAGGCAGGGGCUUCGGAGGACAGCGAGGAGGAGGGUCUGGGCGGCCUGACAUUAGAGGAGCUCCAGCAGGGCCAGGAGGCUGCCCGCGCGCUGGAGGACAUGAUGACGCUGAGUGCUCAGACCCUGGUCCGAGCCGAGGUGGACGAGCUCUACGAGGAAGUGCGUCCCCUGGGCCAGGGUUGCUAUGGCCGCGUCCUUCUGGUCACCCAUCGUCAGAAAGGCACACCCCUGGCACUGAAGCAGCUCCCGAAACCCCGCACGUCCCUCCGUGGCUUCCUGUACGAGUUCUGUGUGGGGCUCUCGCUGGGCGCGCACUCAGCCAUCGUGACGGCCUACGGCAUUGGCAUCGAGUCGGCACACUCCUACAGCUUCCUGACGGAGCCCGUCCUGCACGGGGACCUCAUGGCCUUCAUCCAGCCCAAGGUGCGUAGGCAGACCCCAGGCCGCCUCCGAGUGCCUCACCGGCCUCCCAGGAACGUCCUGAGCAGCCUGGGCCGCAGGAGCCACAGCCACUGCGUUGGGCCUCCCUGGGCCUCCCCUACCCCCCGGAGGCCCCUCGUGGGGCCCACAGGACUCGUGGAGUUGUUAGGCCUCUUUGGAGUUCAUAGACAUCACAGAACUCACACGAUACACCAUGGAGACUCACCAGGCAGCCCCAGGUCACACUGGACCCCAAUCAAGUCACAGGCCCUACAGGGUCACCCGAGGCCCCGCUUAACCUACAGGUCCUACAGGGUCACCCCAGACCCCACUAAACCCACAGGCCUCACAGGUCACACUAGGCCUCACAGGGCCAACUAUUCACCGUCUUCCUUACCGGCCUCCUUGGCGUCCUGGGCCUGCUUCCUGGGUCUCGGUUGCCUUCCGUGGCCCCGGGGCACUGGGCCCUGACCCCUCUCCCCGCAGGUGGGCCUCCCGCAGCCCGCGGUGCACCGCUGCGCCGCCCAGCUGGCCUCCGCCCUGGAGUACAUCCACGCCCGCGGCCUGGUGUACCGGGACCUGAAGCCGGAGAACGUCCUGGUGUGCGACCCGGCCUGCCGGCGCUUCAAGCUGACCGACUUCGGCCACACGAGGCCUCGCGGGACGCUGCUGCGCCUGGCCGGGCCGCCCAUCCCCUACACGGCCCCCGAGCUCUGCGCGCCCCCGCCGCUCCCCGAGGGCCUGCCCAUUCAGCCCGCCCUGGACGCCUGGGCGCUGGGCGUCCUGCUCUUCUGCCUCCUCACGGGCUACUUCCCCUGGGACCGGCCCCUGGCCGAGGCCGACCCCUUCUACGAGGACUUCCUCAUCUGGCAGGCGUCGGGCCAGCCCCGGGACCGCCCUCAGCCCUGGUUCGGCCUGGCCGCCGCGGCCGACGCGCUUCUGCGGGGGCUGCUGGACCCUCACCCCCGAAGGAGGAGCGCUGUGAUCGCCAUCAGGGAGCACCUGGGGCGCCCCUGGAGGCAGCGGGAGGGCGAGGCGGAGGCAGUGGGAGCGGUGGAAGAGGAGGCUGGGCAGUGAGGAGGCCCCGGGGGAUGCAGAAAGGGAAGCCGCCCCACCCGAGGCCCCCAAGGCCAACGGCUUUUGGUGUCUCCUCGGUGUGUUUUCAUCCAUGGGGCUUGGGAUUCCCCUCGGCGUCCUCCUCCUCUCUCCUCUCUGCAGGCUGCAUUCCUCCCUUGGUCCAUGAGGGCCUCAGACCUCUGCAUGUCCCUCCAUACCUGCCGCCACCUUCCCCAGGGUCUCAGACCUCCGCGUGGCUCUCGGUACCUGCCGCCACCUUCCCCAGGGCCUCUGCACUUGCUGUUUGCUCAGGGCACUUUAGGCUCAUCCCCUCACCCCUCGCAUUUUUAUUUUUUUUGAGACAGGGUCUCGCUCUGUCUCCCAGGCUGGAGUGCAGUGGUGCUAUCUCUGCUCACUGCAGUCUCAAAAUCCACAGCUCAAGCAAUCUUCCUGCCUCAGCCUCCUGAGUAGCUGGGACUACAGGCAUGCGCCACCACGCUAGGCUAAUUUUUAACUUUUUUUAGAGAUGGAGGGGUCUUGCUAUGUUGCCCAGGUGGGUGUCAACUCCUGGCCUCAAACAAUCCUCCUGCCUCAGCCUCCUGAGUAGCUGGGACUACAGGCAUGCGCCACCACGCUAGGCUAAUUUUUAACUUUUUAAAAAGAUGGUUGGGGGCGGGUCUUGCUGUGUUGCUCAGGCUAGUCUCAAAUUCCUGGCCUGGAGCGAGUCUCCCACCUCGGCCUCCCGCAGUGCUGGGAUUACAGCUGCGCGUUGUAAAUGCUUACUGUCUGCCUCCUCAUCCCCCCACUCUGCUGUUGCUCUAGGACGUGUAUCCUCUUCUAACUGCAUGGCUUAUUUUUUGUGGUUAUUUUGUGAGCUCCUGGAGUCGGGGGUCUUUGCCGCCUUCCGUCUGCUGACAGACCCCAUGUACUCAGCGAUGGCCUGCAGCAGGGAUCAGGAAAUGUCUGUUAAAUAAAUUAGCCUGUCUGGUGUGGCGCAGCCUCCCCUCCGUCCCUGUCCUCCCGCCGUCCUCUCUCCUUCUCUCCGGCCGGGUCUCCCUCCCACCUGGCACCACCCUCUCUGUGAUGUGUUUUGCCUUCUCUCGCCCCAGCCACUCUGCAAAUAAACUCCAUCUGGCGCUCAGA